CCUUCCCUUCUGCUGGGCCUCAGGUGAGACUGCAGCUCCAGUCAUCAUCUUGAUUGCAGCCCACAGAAACUACCAACCCACAGAAACUGCAUAUGCAAAGAUCAUGUUCACUCCUGGCUGGAUAAUUCAUUCUUUCUUUGUGAAAUAGCUGUGGCAGAGGGAGCCAUAAAUAAAAUAAAGCCUCCUAAACAAAGGUUUGCUUUAAUCUGUUCAUAUUGACAAUAUCUAGUAAAUUCUGAUAUUUCAAACAACUCACCAUAACGGGUAUAGAUCUGGGUUUUUAAGAAAUUGACAUGAUUUAUCCAGACACAUUUGUGGGUUUUCUUUGAAAUAGUAGAGCUUUACUGACUAUGACACUUUGCAUUUUAAAGAAAUUUCAUUGCUUUCUCUUGUGUGUCAUAGAUAAUUUUUAUAUAACUGAAUUGUGAUUCUCCAGUAGAUAAAUGGACAAGAAACAUAAACAUAUAAUUCUCAAAAGAGAAAACACAAAGCAAAAACGGCUAAUUAACAUAUGUUCAGUGCAUAUAUUCAGUCUCAUUAGUGAUGAAAGAAAUACAAAUUUAAGAAAUAUGUCAUGGUGACUUACCUCCUUGUUGACACGAGCAAAGGUAAAAGCAACAGGAAUACAGAAGACUGGCUAGAGAGCAGUUAGAUGGGCCUGUCACCUACUGAGGAAGGUUGGAGACAGGUGGAUUCCCUGGGUUCUGUAAGGCUGCAAGAACUGGAAACAUGCUCAGGUUACCUUAGACAGCAGUAUCUUGUGAAAUAAAUGCCUGAGGGAGGGAAAAUGGGAAACAUGUGAUCAGUCCUCGUGGCACCUAGAAUGUUCUUCAGGAUCCACAAUUCUAGAAGUUCAAGGGCAGCUGUGGUCACUCAACUUGCUUGAGUUGUUCCUACAGAAUCUGGCAUACAUUGCUCGCUCCCAUAGUGCUCUGUUGUAUGGUAAUACAGGACUCUCUCUGAAGACUGACUCCAACUGGCUAAAUCAAAAAGGAAAGCAUUGGUCCUCUUGAAUGGAAGGUCUAAGGACAGGAUUUGCUCAGGACAGCUGGAGCUGAGGGCUUUAGUGGAGGUAUUCUCUGUCUCUGUCAGCCCUGCUGUCCUUUGAACUGGCUUCACUUUAAAGCAGGCUUUUUCCAUGUGGUGGCCCCUGGUAGGUCACUUCACAUCUCUAAUCCUGUUUCCUCAUUCUAGAAAAAUGGAGCUACUAGCCACCUGCAUAAGUACAAUGUGAGGAUCCCAUGAGAUAGACUAUAUGUAAAUGCUUUCAAGCUGCCACAUUUCAGAGGACUUUAUUAUUUGAUAUGAGCUCAGUGGCCUGUUUUGGAACAGUCUUUAACAUGGCAUCUGUACCGUCUUCCCUGUUUCUGAUUAUUAAUAAGAUGGUAUUGCUUUUGUUAAGCAAGCCUGCUCUGCAACUUGGCACAGAGGGGGAAAAAAGUCAUCCUCUUUAUCAAGAAUAUCAAGAAUGAGGGGCAUUAUUAUUUUUUUUUAAAUUGGCAUUUAAAAAAAUUAAGUUCUAAGGCCCUGGGAGCCUAUGGAAGAGUCUCAAGGACCACAAUGUGUGUGGAAGGGCCGGAUAGCAGUGGGCAAGGCUGACUGGGUGGAGCUGCCCUGUUUAAUAAGAGCAGGCCUGCUUUUGUCUGUUUUCUACACCAUGAUUCUGGAUGAGAUUUUACAUCAAAAAGGAGAGUGGUAAUAUGAUUAAAAUAGGAGCAGCUUUGGCAGCAAAACAGAAGAAAUGAGCCAAACGCUGACAUUAAUUGACUAAAAGCUAAUGAAAGCAGAACUGAAUCAAUCAAUUACAGCAAAAUUGAACAUCACUUGACAAUAUCUAGAAUUCAAUAUUUUUUAAGUAGAUCAGUAAUAGCUCAAAGUGGUAUGUAUUUCAUUGGCCUAGGCCUGAAAUUCUCCUCAUUCCUCUGGCUCACCUCUGGGACUAAGGACACUGAGAAGCCUCUGCAAUGGAUGGGCUCAACCGGCCAACCAGCCCUCCUACACUAUAUGGUAUACAAUAUUAGUGUUUACCAACCCCUCCUUGUUCUGGCCAAUGCAAUGUGAGUAGAAUUAGUGUGUGUUUUCUCUUUGACUCUGAGCAAGUUGCCGACCUGUCUCAUUUUUCUCAUCUAUAAAGCAUAAUAUCUACAUUACAGGGUUGCUGAAGAGAUCAAAUUAUAAACACACACAUGCACACAUAGCUAGCAUUUAACAGUAUCUAACAGUUGGUAGGGAAUCAAUAAACCUAGGUACCCUUUCUCUCUGUUCCCUUCCUUCUAACCAUUUCUAAGCUCGGUAAUGUGCUGUUUUGAUCUCACAGGCUCUAGAACUAGGACUCCUUAAAGUCCUUACUCCAAGGUCUGUGUCCUCUACAUCCCUGCUAGGGCUUUGAAACUAGAAGUGAAUGCUGCCAAAUCCUCUGACUUAUCGCUCUUUGUAGUGCACUUCAACUCUAAAGACGAAAUCACGGCCAGGGCGACAGGCUAAAGUCUGAGUCAGGGUGAGCUUUUGGGGAAACGGCGUGGAGCGGGUGGUGGUGUCAGCUCUCUCCUCGCCUACACUUCAGCUCCUUUCUGCCCACAUCCAUUCAGGGCAUUGCCCUGUUUGUCUCCUCAGCUGUCUUCUGUAUUAACCUCCAGCCUGUUGGGUGCAUUCAGUUCUGCCAGCUGGACUUUCAAUAUGUAUUUAAAAAGACACAUAAACAAAAAACAAAAACAAAAACAAAAAAACUUUACUAGAAGCCAAAGGAAAACCAUCAUAUUCAAAAAUAUAAAUAUAAAAGCAAAGAAAUGCAUACAUUUACUGGACAAAGAGGUCUCAUCUUGAGUAAACUGGGAGCACUCCGAGAUGUCUGGAGGUCUUGGAGGCUACACGCUAUCCAUUGAUACCUCCUGUCAAAUUCUGAACAUGCAGAAAUUACCAGAUCUCAAAGUCCUCAUUUCUUGUUGAAUUUUAGUGAAAAAAACUUCCCUGGAUCCCACCGUAGUUGAGUCUUGGAACAGGGUGUUAAUCUUUAUAUUAUAAAAUGUCCUUGACUAGAGAUAAUAGGCAGUAUGAAACAUUAUAUUUUUAAAAAGGAAACAUAAUAUUGAAAAAAAAAGAGAAAUACUGUUGCAGUGACUUGGAAUCCCCAGUUCUCAAAGGGAAGAAGGCCAAUAAAGAAGUGGGAGAAGAAAGUCUGAGAACCGCAUGAAAAGGGUCCUGUUCCCACUAGGACCAUGGUCCACUCACCAAAUUAUCAGAGACGUUUGAACCAGAGCAACUCCAUCUUGAAUAGGAGCUGGGUAAAAUAAGGCUGAGACCUACUGGGCUACACUCCCAGGAGGUUAGACAUUCUAAGUCACAGAAUGAGAUAGAAGGUAGGCACAAGACACAGGUCAUAAAGACCUUGCUGAUAAAACAGGUUGCAGUAAGGAAGCUGGCCAAAACCCACCAAAACCAGGAUGGCAAUGAGAGUGUCCUCUGGUCGUCACUGCUACGGUCUCACCAGCUCCAUGACAGUUUACAAAUGCCACUGCAACGUCGGGAAGCUACCCUAUAUGGUCUAAAAAGGGGAGGCAUGAAUAAUUUCCCCCGCUUAGCAUAUAAUCAAGAAAUAACCCUAAAAAUGGACAACCAACAGCCCUUGGGGGUGCUCUGCCUAUGAGUAGCCAUUCUUUUAUUCCUUUAGUUUCUUAAUUACUUGCUUUCACUUUACUCCAUGGACUCCCCUCAAAUUCUUUCUUGCGCAAAAUCCAAGAACCCUCUCUUGGGGUCUGGAUCGGGACCCAUUUUCGGUAAUAAACUUGUAGCAUUUGGUGUUUUAAUGUUUGUGUUUUCUUGACUUGUUACCUCAUUUAGCCUCAACUGUUUAAAGAUGGUCUUUUUGGCCAUUUUAUUCAGCUUUAAUUGUUCUAAGGGGAGUGAAGAAAUGGUCAUUUACUUUGAAAAAUCAGAGGGAACGUGUUGAUGCGGGAAGCAGCUAAUCCUUGGGGUACAGUGGCCCUUGGUAGUGCAGGAAAGUCCUGGGGGCCACCUCUAACCCACCUUCCUCCUCUACAGCAUCUCCCACUGUAGUCAUUCUCUACCGAAGCCCCAGAAGGUGCGGCACUUUGCCACGACAGAGUACUGGGUUCAUGUUUCUUUCCGAGGCGGGCCAAGAGCUCUCAGCCCACUGGCAGUGGCGAGAUGACGGACACCCAGCGAGUCCAAUGGGCGUCGAACGCGUCUAGGCUUGGUGGACUUGUCAGCGCCUGCCUGGCUUCGGUCCCCAACUUGAGCACCGGCCCUUUCCUGCAUGCCCCUAACCCUCGCAACGCUAAACAGUGAAAAAAAAAAAAAGACAAAAACAAAAAGCAUCUCAACACACACACACACACACACACACACACACACACACACACACACACACACACACACACACACACACACACACACGGAUCCGCGUUCAGAAAGGCGUGCACUUCCUACGCCUGAUCCCCCGCAUCGCAACCUCGCAGCUUCCCCGGCGUGCAGCGCUCAUUUACCAAUUCCCUUCCUGGGAGUUGCGGCUUCCCUCGCUCGGCCCCACUCCCGUUUACCCUUUCCCCAGCUCCCGCCUUAGCCAGGGGCUUCCCCGCCUGCCGCUAGGGCUCGGGCCGAAGCGCCGCUCAGCGCCAGCCUGCCGCUCCCCGGGCUCCACUUUCACUUUCGGUCCUGGGGGAGCUAGGCCGGCGGCAGUGGUGGUGGCGGCGGCGCAAGGGUGAGGGCGGCCCCAGAACCCCAGGUAGGUAGAGCAAGAAGAUGGUGUUUCUGCCCCUCAAAUGGUCCCUUGCAACCAUGUCAUUUCUACUUUCCUCACUGUUGGCUCUCUUAACUGUGUCCACUCCUUCAUGGUGUCAGAGCACUGAAGCAUCUCCAAAACGUAGUGAUGGGACACCAUUUCCUUGGAAUAAAAUACGACUUCCUGAGUACGUCAUCCCAGUUCAUUAUGAUCUCUUGAUCCAUGCAAACCUUACCACGCUGACCUUCUGGGGAACCACGAAAGUAGAAAUCACAGCCAGUCAGCCCACCAGCACCAUCAUCCUGCAUAGUCACCACCUGCAGAUAUCUAGGGCCACCCUCAGGAAGGGAGCUGGAGAGAGGCUAUCGGAAGAACCCCUGCAGGUCCUGGAACACCCCCGUCAGGAGCAAAUUGCACUGCUGGCUCCCGAGCCCCUCCUUGUCGGGCUCCCGUACACAGUUGUCAUUCACUAUGCUGGCAAUCUUUCGGAGACUUUCCACGGAUUUUACAAAAGCACCUACAGAACCAAGGAAGGGGAACUGAGGAUACUAGCAUCAACACAAUUUGAACCCACUGCAGCUAGAAUGGCCUUUCCCUGCUUUGAUGAACCUGCCUUCAAAGCAAGUUUCUCAAUCAAAAUUAGAAGAGAGCCAAGGCACCUAGCCAUCUCCAAUAUGCCAUUGGUGAAAUCUGUGACUGUUGCUGAAGGACUCAUAGAAGACCAUUUUGAUGUCACUGUGAAGAUGAGCACCUAUCUGGUGGCCUUCAUCAUUUCAGAUUUUGAGUCUGUCAGCAAGAUAACCAAGAGUGGAGUCAAGGUUUCUGUUUAUGCUGUGCCAGACAAGAUAAAUCAAGCAGAUUAUGCACUGGAUGCUGCGGUGACUCUUCUAGAAUUUUAUGAGGAUUAUUUCAGCAUACCGUAUCCCCUACCCAAACAAGAUCUUGCUGCUAUUCCCGACUUUCAGUCUGGUGCUAUGGAAAACUGGGGACUGACAACAUAUAGAGAAUCUGCUCUGUUGUUUGAUGCAGAAAAGUCUUCUGCAUCAAGUAAGCUUGGCAUCACAAUGACUGUGGCCCAUGAACUGGCUCACCAGUGGUUUGGGAACCUGGUCACUAUGGAAUGGUGGAAUGAUCUUUGGCUAAAUGAAGGAUUUGCCAAAUUUAUGGAGUUUGUGUCUGUCAGUGUGACCCAUCCUGAACUGAAAGUUGGAGAUUAUUUCUUUGGCAAAUGUUUUGACGCAAUGGAGGUAGAUGCUUUAAAUUCCUCACACCCUGUGUCUACACCUGUGGAAAAUCCUGCUCAGAUCCGGGAGAUGUUUGAUGAUGUUUCUUAUGAUAAGGGAGCUUGUAUUCUGAAUAUGCUAAGGGAGUAUCUUAGUGCUGACGCAUUUAAAAGUGGUAUUGUACAGUAUCUCCAGAAGCAUAGCUAUAAAAAUACAAAAAACGAGGACCUGUGGGAUAGUAUGGCAAGUAUUUGCCCUACAGAUGGUGUAAAAGGGAUGGAUGGCUUUUGCUCUAGAAGUCAACAUUCAUCUUCAUCCUCACAUUGGCAUCAGGAAGGGGUGGAUGUGAAAACCAUGAUGAACACUUGGACACUGCAGAAGGGUUUUCCCCUAAUAACCAUCACAGUGAGGGGGAGGAAUGUACACAUGAAGCAAGAGCACUACAUGAAGGGCUCUGACGGCGCCCCGGACACUGGGUACCUGUGGCAUGUUCCAUUGACAUUCAUCACCAGCAAAUCCGACAUGGUCCAUCGAUUUUUGCUAAAAACAAAAACAGAUGUGCUCAUCCUCCCAGAAGAGGUGGAAUGGAUCAAAUUUAAUGUGGGCAUGAAUGGCUAUUACAUUGUGCAUUACGAGGAUGAUGGAUGGGACUCUUUGACUGGCCUUUUAAAAGGAACACACACAGCAGUCAGCAGUAAUGAUCGGGCGAGUCUCAUUAACAAUGCAUUUCAGCUCGUCAGCAUUGGGAAGCUGUCCAUUGAAAAGGCCUUGGAUUUAUCCCUGUACUUGAAACAUGAAACUGAAAUUAUGCCCGUGUUUCAAGGUUUGAAUGAGCUGAUUCCUAUGUAUAAGUUAAUGGAGAAAAGAGAUAUGAAUGAAGUGGAAACUCAAUUCAAGGCCUUCCUCAUCAGGCUGCUAAGGGACCUCAUUGAUAAGCAGACAUGGACAGACGAGGGCUCAGUCUCAGAGCGAAUGCUGCGGAGUCAACUACUACUCCUCGCCUGUGUGCACAACUAUCAGCCGUGCGUACAGAGGGCAGAAGGCUAUUUCAGAAAGUGGAAGGAAUCCAAUGGAAACUUGAGCCUGCCUGUCGACGUGACCUUGGCAGUGUUUGCUGUGGGGGCCCAGAGCACAGAAGGCUGGGAUUUUCUUUAUAGUAAAUAUCAGUUUUCUUUGUCCAGUACUGAGAAAAGCCAAAUUGAAUUUGCCCUCUGCAGAACCCAAAAUAAGGAAAAGCUUCAAUGGCUACUAGAUGAAAGCUUUAAGGGAGAUAAAAUAAAAACUCAGGAGUUUCCACAAAUUCUUACACUCAUUGGCAGGAACCCAGUAGGAUACCCACUGGCCUGGCAAUUUCUGAGGAAAAACUGGAACAAACUUGUACAAAAGUUUGAACUUGGCUCAUCUUCCAUAGCCCACAUGGUAAUGGGUACAACAAAUCAAUUCUCCACAAGAACACGGCUUGAAGAGGUAAAAGGAUUCUUCAGCUCUUUGAAAGAAAAUGGUUCUCAGCUCCGUUGUGUCCAACAGACAAUUGAAACCAUUGAAGAAAACAUCGGUUGGAUGGAUAAGAAUUUUGAUAAAAUCAGAGUGUGGCUGCAAAGUGAAAAGCUUGAACGUUCUCUAUAUCAUCGUUUGAUUCAUUCUACAGUUUAAAAAUUGUAAGGGCCAGGCGCAGUGGCUCAAGCCUGUAAUCCCAGUACUUUGGGAGGUAGAGGUUGGCAGAUCACUUGAGCCCAAGAGCUCGAGACCAGCCUGGCAACAUGGCGAAACCCCCUCUCUACAAAAAAAUACAAAAAUUAGCUGGGUGUGGUGGUGCACGCCUGUAGUCCCAGCUACUCAGGAAGCUAAGGUAGGAGGAUUGCUUGAGCCCAGGAAGCAGAGAUCGCAGUAAGCUGAGAUCACACCACUGCACUCCAGCCUGGGCUAUAGAGUAAGACCCUGUUACAAGACAGACCGAUAGAUAGAUCAAUCAAUAAAUAAAACUUAUAUGUAUGUACACAUACACACACACACAUUUCAAAGAGUGAAAUGUGAAAAAGCACAGUACCUUUGCUGUGUUCUGUGAGGUUUCUGUAGUGGAGGGACAGCUGUCCAGAUCUCCUGAGAGAGCAUCAAUGGGGUCUUGGUCAUCUGCAGGUUUCUGAGAUAUGAGUAGAAAUAACCAUCAGUGAAGAAGCAGAAGGCAAAAUGCAAUAUGGGGUCUUUUCCCACAUCACUUACAAAUAAAAGAUGUUUCUAUAAGAAAAAAA